ACUAUGGCGGUUGGAGGAACGGCAGUGAUCACACGUCGGCUGCUGGGAAGAUCUGGAUUCUCGUUUCAGGUCACCAUCAGAAAAGCUAAGUUUGCUGUAUAGUGAGGAUCAGGAGAUCUGAUCCUGAUUGCAGAACCUUCCCUGAUUACAGAAUCUUGGGAUUGUUGAGAGGAUUACAUGUAAAGUACCAGGACAGUGCAUGGCACAUAUGAUUUCACAAAAGUUCAUCUUCAUUGCAGAUACCUGCCUUUCUUUCUAGGUUGUAUCUCCCACUUCACCCUUCUAGACCAUCCCAGAAGAUCUAUAAGAUUUCAUCUGGGAAAUCACUAGGAGUUCUUGGAAGGGAAAGAAGGAAGAUUGUUGGUUGGAAUAAAAACAGGGUUGAAUGAGUUCCAGAAAGCAGGGUUCUCAACCUCGUGGACAGCAAUCUGCAGAAGAAGAGAACUUCAAAAAACCAACUAGAAGCAACAUGCAGAGAAGUAAAAUGAGAGGGGCCUCCUCAGGAAAGAAGACAGCUGGUCCACAGCAGAAAAAUCUUGAACCAGCUCUCCCAGGAAGAUGGGGUGGUCGCUCUGCAGAGAACCCCCCUUCAGGAUCCGUGAGGAAGACCAGAAAGAACAAGCAGAAGACUCCUGGAAACGGAGAUGGUGGCAGUACCAGCGAAGCACCUCAGCCCCCUCGGAAGAAAAGGGCCCGGGCAGACCCCACUGUUGAAAGUGAGGAGGCGUUUAAGAAUAGAAUGGAGGUUAAAGUGAAGAUUCCUGAAGAAUUAAAACCAUGGCUUGUUGAGGACUGGGACUUAGUUACCAGGCAGAAGCAGCUGUUUCAACUCCCUGCCAAGAAAAAUGUAGAUGCAAUUCUGGAGGAGUAUGCAAAUUGCAAGAAAUCGCAGGGAAAUGUUGAUAAUAAGGAAUAUGCGGUUAAUGAAGUUGUGGCAGGAAUAAAAGAAUAUUUCAAUGUGAUGUUGGGCACUCAGCUGCUCUACAAAUUUGAGAGGCCCCAGUAUGCUGAAAUCCUCUUGGCUCACCCUGAUGCUCCAAUGUCCCAGGUUUAUGGAGCACCACACCUACUGAGAUUAUUUGUAAGAAUUGGAGCAAUGUUGGCCUAUACGCCCCUUGAUGAGAAAAGCCUUGCAUUAUUGUUGGGCUAUUUGCAUGAUUUCCUAAAAUAUCUGGCAAAGAAUUCUGCAUCUCUCUUUACUGCCAGUGAUUACAAAGUGGCUUCUGCUGAGUACCACCGCAAAGCCCUGUGAGCGUCUACAGACAGCUCACCAUUUUUGUCCUGUAUCUGUAAACACUUUUUGUUCUUAGUCUUUUUCUUGUAAAAUUGAUGUUCUUUAAAAUCGUUAAUGUAUAACAGGGCUUAUGUUUCAGUUUGUUUUCCGUUCUGUUUUAAACAGAAAAUAAAAGGAGUGUAAGCUCCUUUUCUCAUUUCAAAGUUGCUACCAGUGUAUGCAGUAAUUAGAACAAAGAAGAAACAUUCAGUAGAACAUUUUAUUGCCUAGUUGACAACAUUGCUUGAAUGCUGGUGGUUCCUAUCCCUUUGACACUACACAAUUUUCUAAUAUGUGUUAAUGCUAUGUGACAAAACGCCCUGAUUCCUAGUGCCAAAGGUUCAACUUAAUGUAUAUACCUGAAAACCCAUGCAUUUGUGCUCUUUUUUUUUUUUUAUGGUGCUUGAAGUAAAACAGCCCAUCCUCUGCAAGUCCAUCUAUGUUGUUCUUAGGCAUUCUAUCUUUGCUCAAAUUGUUGAAGGAUGGUGAUUUGUUUCAUGGUUUUUGUAUUUGAGUCUAAUGCACGUUCUAACAUGAUAGAGGCAAUGCAUUAUUGUGUAGCCACGGUUUUCUGGAAAAGUUGAUAUUUUAGGAAUUGUAUUUCAGAUCUUAAAUAAAAUUUGUUUCUAAAUUUCAAAGCAA